GCAGUCGGAGGCGGCCGGCUGGGCGUGCGCUCGCUCCCCGAAGCCGGGGCUGGGCCGGAGCCGGGCGAGGGCUGGGAGCUGGGCCGGGUCCGGGGACAGCGGGCGAGGGGCAGCUGCCGGAGCCGGGCAGCCAGGCCGCUCAGGGCAGGGGACAGCUGGCGCCGGUUCUGCGGUCUCCGGGGCCCAGAUGUGAGGCGGCGGCGCCCCCGGCCCGAGAGCGCACGAUGGGGGCCCCGCUCGCCGUAGCGCUGGGCGCCCUCCACUACCUGGCACUUUUCCUGCAACUCGGCGGCGCCACGCGGCCCGCCGGCCACGCGCCCUGGGACAACCACGUCUCCGGCCACGCCCUGUUCACAGAGACACCCCAUGACAUGACAGCACGGACGGGCGAGGACGUGGAGAUGGCCUGCUCCUUCCGCGGCAGCGGCUCCCCCUCCUACUCGCUGGAGAUCCAGUGGUGGUAUGUACGGAGCCACCGGGACUGGACCGACAAGCAGGCGUGGGCCUCGAACCAGCUAAAAGCAUCUCAGCAGGAAGACGCAGGGAAGGAGGCAACCAAAAUAAGUGUGGUCAAGGUGGUGGGCAGCAACAUCUCCCACAAGCUGCGCCUGUCCCGGGUGAAGCCCACGGACGAAGGCACCUACGAGUGCCGCGUCAUCGACUUCAGCGACGGCAAGGCCCGGCACCACAAGGUCAAGGCCUACCUGCGGGUGCAGCCAGGGGAGAACUCCGUCCUGCAUCUGCCCGAAGCCCCUCCCGCCGCGCCCGCCCCGCCGCCCCCCAAGCCAGGCAAGGAGCUGAGGAAGCGCUCGGUGGACCAGGAGGCCUGCAGCCUCUAGACUGAUGCCCCUGCCCCCGCCCAUCCGCCCCCACGCUGUACAGAGUGCAUGAGGAGCCGCCGGACCACCGGGGACCGACUGCCUGCGUCCAGCCGCGCCCCAUCCCCGAGGCCGCCUGUGGCCACCAUGUCGGCCCUCUUUCCACCACCCCUUGCUCAGCAUGUAAGCCCCACCCACCCCUGCCCUUUCAGACCCCUGCGGUGACCUGGCUCGGAGAAGGUGGCCCUGGGCACCAAGGGGCCAACCGCCCUGAACACUGGGGCAGGGACCAUGCUGGGGCCCGGGGCCACCCCCUUCCUGUCACCAGCUUCUGUGGAGUCCAGUGUUUUGCUUUGCUUGCUUGUCCCCCAUCCUGUCCUGAGCCGGGGCCCCCCAGCCUCGCCUCCCUCCUCCUACCAUCCCUCACUUGGACCUGGGGGUGUGGACAGUGACCCCUCCCUGAAUAUGGACUUGAAUCUUCUGAGCAGAACUAGGGCCUCUCCCCUGGUGAAGACCCAGGGAACCCAGGAGGGCCCUUCUGGGGCAGUGGCUCUGCAGGGUCACUCAUGGAGGCCUAGGGGAACAGCGAGAUGCCCCACCACCUCCUGGCGAGUCCUUCCUGUUCAGCUCCCUGUGCGACCCUCCAGGGAUGCAGGGGAUCCAGGAUUCUCUGCCCUGUCACACGGCGAGUCAGAAGGGAGGGGCCUUUCCCUCGGACCCAUGGCCCCAGGCAGAGUUUUGCACCAGCAGGACCCCUUUGAGGGCCUUCAAGGCUCUCCCAGGAGUCCCCCUCUGCCGGCCCCCCAAUGCCCCAGCUCCCUCUUGGGUCCUGUGCCAAGUCCGCCCCAGGGCCUGGGGCUGUUGGGAGCCAAGGGCCCCCUGGUACUCAGUUCCCUCACGAUUCCCGAUCACGGGCACACCUGCCCCCUGGUUAUUUGUAAAUAUUUCUAUUGGACCCAAUUCUCCUCGGAAUUGGCUGGCACCUCUGGCUGCCGCAGCUCAGUGAUGACGUGGGGGAGGUGGGAGAGGCCGAGGGCUUUGCCUAGGGGUGGGUUGCCCUGUAUACAUGAUCCAGUCUGUGACUACCAGCCAACCUGAAUAAAGCGGUUUUAAAAAAA